CCCAAAGUUCGAAACCAACAGAACGAAAAGCAACGAAGCACACUUAAAGUGAGGAACCCGGCAAGCGGCGAAAUUCUUGCUGAAGAGAAGAAAAAGCGAAAGGUUUUCCGCUGCAACCAAUCAGAUGAGAGGAUUCUUGGCACGCCCCUUUCUAUCUACCAAUCAACAUCUAGCUCAAUGGGGCAGUCCAUUGCCACAGGGAAAGGGCUUGGUGCAGCUUCCCUCACAACACACACGUCAUUCUAGGCCAUUCCACGAACUGUGCUCAAAAGAGGAAAACAGUGCAACAGUUCCAAAGCUGAUCAGUCUCGUGGUGAGCAGCGAAACUAUAGACUUCUCUAACAAAACCAUGGAUUCUAGGAGGGACUGGGAAAGAGAAAAACGAAUUCUGGAAGGCAAACUACAACUCCCAAAGGCCCUUGCGCGGACUCAGCGCGCGAGGGACGAAGGGCGGGCGUGGACGAGCCGGUGGCUGCAGCGGCGGCGGUCCCCGGAGUCCUGUGAAGCGCCCCUGUCCGCGCCUCUGUGGGGCCCUCAGAGAGGGCUGCCAGGACGCGAGCCACUGAGGAGCCGCUCAGCCAGCGCCAUAGCCCUUAGGACUAUCGGUCACAUUCUCGCGCUCCUGCUCCGGCUCCUCCAUCUUGGCCUCGGCAGUGGCGGCUGCCGGGAGGAUGUGCCGCCUUCUGGCAGGGGGAAGAAGGAGGAGAAGAUGAAGAAGCACCGGCGGGCCUUGGCCCUGGUCUCCUGCCUCUUUCUGUGCUCUCUGGUCUGGCUUCCCAGCUGGCGUGUAUGUUGUAAAGAGAGUUCUUCAGCUUCAGCGUCAUCAUAUUACUCUCAAGAUGACAACUGCGCACUAGAAAAUGAAGAUGUACAAUUCCAGAAAAAGAAUACAGAGUCAAAAAAGUUAAGUCCACCGGUGGUGGAGACACUCCCUACAGUUGAUUUGCAUGAAGAGUCUUCCAAUGCAGUUGUGGACAGUGAAACUGUUGAAAAUAUUUCCAGCUCAUCUACCUCAGAAAUCACUCCAAUCUCAAAGCUUGAUGAAAUAGAAAAAUCUGGUACUAUUCCGAUAGCCAAACCAAGUGAAACUGAGCAGUCUGAAACUGAUUGUGAUGUUGGUGAGGCCCUUGAUGCUAGUGCUCCAAUUGAACAACCUUCCUUUGUCAGUCCACCUGACAGCCUUGUUGGCCAGCAUAUAGAAAAUGUAUCAUCUUCACAUGGUAAAGGAAAGAUAACAAAAUCAGAAUUUGAAUCAAAAGUUUCAGCAAGUGAACAGGGCGGUGGUGAUCCAAAAUCUGCAUUGAAUGCUUCAGAUAAUUUAAAAAAUGAGAGCUCUGAUUAUACAAAACCAGGAGACAUUGACCCUACAUCAGUAGCAAGUCCCAAAGAUCCAGAAGAUAUACCAACAUUUGAUGAAUGGAAGAAGAAAGUUAUGGAAGUAGAAAAAGAAAAAAGUCAGUCGAUGCAUGCAUCUUCUAAUGGAGGUUCACAUGCCACCAAAAAGGUCCAGAAAAAUCGAAAUAAUUAUGCCUCAGUAGAAUGUGGUGCCAAAAUUCUAGCAGCUAAUCCAGAAGCCAAGAGCACAUCUGCUAUUCUUAUAGAAAAUAUGGAUCUUUACAUGUUGAAUCCUUGCAGCACUAAAAUUUGGUUUGUUAUUGAACUUUGUGAACCAAUUCAAGUAAAACAGCUUGAUAUUGCAAAUUAUGAAUUAUUUUCUUCUACUCCUAAAGAUUUUCUGGUUUCUAUCAGUGACAGAUAUCCAACAAAUAAGUGGAUUAAGCUGGGUACUUUUCAUGGUAGAGAUGAGCGGAAUGUACAGAGUUUCCCUUUAGAUGAACAGAUGUAUGCAAAAUAUGUCAAGGUUGAGUUGCUAUCACAUUUUGGAUCAGAGCACUUUUGUCCAUUAAGCCUUAUAAGGGUAUUUGGCACUAGCAUGGUGGAAGAAUAUGAAGAAAUUGCUGAUUCCCAGUAUCACUCAGAACGCCAGGAACUAUUUGAUGAGGACUAUGAUUAUCCACUGGAUUAUAAUACUGGAGAGGAUAAAUCCUCAAAAAAUCUUCUUGGUUCUGCUACAAAUGCCAUUCUAAAUAUGGUGAAUAUUGCUGCUAAUAUUCUGGGAGCAAAAACUGAAGACCUGACAGAAGGAAAUAAAAGUAUAUCUGAGAAUGCCACUGCCACAGCUGCACCUAAAAUGCCUGAAUCAACUCCUGUUUCAACUCCUGUUCCAUCUCCUGAGUAUGUAACCACUGAAGUACACACACAUGACAUGGAGCCGUCAACACCAGAUACUCCAAAAGAGAGUCCCAUUGUACAGUUAGUUCAAGAGGAGGAAGAGGAGGCAAGUCCAUCUACAGUGACCCUUCUGGGCAGCGGUGAACAGGAAGAUGAAUCAUCACCCUGGUUUGAGUCAGAGACACAAAUAUUUUGCAGUGAACUGACCACAAUUUGUUGUAUUUCUAGUUUUUCAGAAUACAUAUAUAAAUGGUGUUCAGUUAGAGUUGCUCUUUAUCGGCAGCGCAGCCGAACUGCUUUGAGUAAAGGAAAAGAUUAUCUUGUGUUAGCUCAACCACCCUUACUACUUCCUGCGGAAUCAGUAGAUGUUUCAGUAUUGCAACCUCUGAGUGGAGAAUUGGAAAAUACGAAUAUAGAAAGGGAAGCUGAAACUGUUGUUCUGGGUGAUUUAAGUAGUAGUAUGCACCAGGAUGACUUGGUGAAUCACACUGUAGAUGCAGUUGAACUUGAACCAAGCCAUUCUCAAACUCUUUCUCAGUCUCUUCUUUUAGAUAUUACCCCAGAAAUCAAUCCCUUGCCUAAAAUAGAAGUAUCUGAGUCUGUUGAAUAUGAGGCAGGACAUAUACCAUCACCAGUGAUUCCCCAAGAGAGUUCUGUUGAGAUCGAUAAUGAAACAGAACAAAAGUCUGAGAGCUUUAGUUCUAUAGAGAAACCAUCUAUUACCUAUGAAACAAAUAAAGUUAAUGAGUUAAUGGAUAAUAUUAUAAAAGAAGAUGUGAACUCCAUGCAAAUUUUCACAAAGCUGUCUGAAACAAUAGUGCCACCAAUAAAUACAGCCACUGUACCCGACAAUGAAGAUGGGGAAGCCAAAAUGAAUAUAGCUGACACAGCAAAGCAAACUUUGAUUUCUGUUGUGGAUUCUUCUUCAUUACCUGAAGUAAAAGAAGAAGAACAGUCUCCAGAAGAUGCCCUUUUGAGAGGGUUACAGAGGACAGCUACAGAUUUUUAUGCUGAAUUGCAAAAUUCUACAGAUCUAGGAUAUGCUAAUGGAAAUCUUGUACAUGGAUCAAACCAAAAGGAGUCAGUAUUUAUGAGACUUAAUAAUCGUAUUAAAGCCUUAGAAGUUAACAUGUCUCUCAGUGGUCGCUAUCUGGAGGAGCUUAGCCAAAGGUACCGAAAACAAAUGGAAGAAAUGCAAAAGGCUUUCAAUAAAACAAUCGUGAAACUUCAGAAUACUUCAAGAAUAGCAGAGGAGCAGGAUCAGCGGCAAACUGAAGCCAUCCAGUUGCUACAGGCACAGCUGACCAACAUGACACAGCUUGUUUCAAAUUUAUCAGCAACAGUAGCAGAAUUGAAACGGGAGGUUUCAGAUCGACAAAGCUAUCUUGUCAUAUCUUUGGUUCUUUGUGUUGUCUUGGGACUGAUGCUUUGUAUGCAGCGUUGUCGAAAUACUUCUCAAUUUGAUGGAGAUUAUAUUUCAAAACUUCCUAAAAGUAAUCAGUAUCCAAGCCCUAAAAGGUGUUUCUCUUCCUAUGAUGAUAUGAAUUUGAAAAGAAGAACUUCAUUCCCACUCAUGAGAUCCAAGUCUCUACAGUUAACUGGCAAAGAAGUAGACCCAAAUGAUUUGUACAUUGUAGAACCCCUCAAGUUUUCUCCAGAAAAGAAGAAGAAGCGCUGCAAGUACAAAAUUGAAAAAAUUGAGACCAUAAAGCCUGAAGAACCAUUGCACCCCAUAGCCAAUGGCGACAUAAAAGGAAGAAAGCCCUUUACGAACCAGAGAGAUUUUUCUAAUAUGGGAGAAGUUUAUCACUCUUCUUAUAAAGGUCCUCCAUCUGAAGGAAGCUCAGAAACUUCAUCACAGUCAGAAGAGUCCUAUUUUUGUGGCAUUUCAGCUUGCACAAGUCUGUGCAAUGGACAGUCUCAAAAGACAAAAACUGAGAAGAGGGCUUUAAAACGAAGACGAUCUAAAGUCCAAGACCAAGGAAAAUUGAUAAAAACUCUAAUACAGACUAAGUCGGGAUCAUUGCCGAGCCUGCAUGACAUAAUCAAAGGAAACAAAGAGAUCACCGUGGGAACAUUUGGUGUUACAGCAGUCUCGGGACAUAUCUAAAAUUAAUUGAACUUUUCAUACAGAAGACUUUUUUGUUGUUGUUCUUUGAAGAACAGUCUGUAGUAUUUGAAGGGUUUGGGGGAGGGAGAAAAUAUUAAUGGGAAAGGCAUUCAGAAAUUAUGGUUUCUACCUUUUUAAAAAGUAGAUGGGAUUGUGUCAAUCUUGGUUAAUGAGCUACAGUUUUACAAAGCUGAUCACUUCCUAUAAGGACAAUGGUAGACAUUUUAUAAAGAUGUUUUUUCACAAGAUUAAUUACUGGGACAAAAGUAAUUUGGAAGCCCAGUUCCUUAGGUGGGAUAGGAAUGAAAGCCUAAACCUCUUCCUUUAGCUUUGUUCCUAUUUCUUGCACCUUCCCAUAUUUAUGUGCCUUUUGUCUAUUUAUAAUGCCACUGGAAGAGGAGGGAUAACUUUUUCUGUUAUUUGAUUUCUUUUAUAACUUUGUUAGGUUUUUGAAGCUGCAAACACUACAAUGCUUUGAGGGGGUCUGUGCCUGAAGCUCAGGAGUGUGGAUCAGACAGUCUAAAGAUCCUAAAAACUUGCCAACUGGAUCUUUGUUUAGCAAACUCACUGGAAAUGAACACUUAAUGGAAUUUUUAAGUCUGUUCUGUUAGGUAGAUGGUGAUGCUCUUGUUAUUUUCACUUAUUCAGACUGGAUUACUUCUUACUUAGUUACUAACUCAAUGAGGAAAAAUCCCUACAGGAUCUUUUUUUGCAAACAACUGAUAUAUGCAGACAAAUUUUUGACAAAUUCACCUUUUAAACACACUUAACCAUUUGUGAAGGUUUUCUUUAGCUUACAUUUUAAACAUACACAAUAAACACUAAUCCUCCAAACUUUCACUGUUUUUAUUAGUAUGAAUAUAAAAUUUGAAGGUUUGGCCAAUUAGUACAAGUCUCAUGAUAUAAUCACUGCCUGCAUACAUAUGCACAGAUCCAGUUAGUGAGUUUGUCAAGCUUAAUCUAAUUGGUUAAGUCUAAAGAGAUUAUUAUUCCUUGAUGUUUGCUUUGUAUUGGCUACAAAUGUGCAGAGGUAAUACAUAUGUGAUGUCGAUGUCUCUGUCUUUUUUUUUGUCUUUAAAAAAUAAUUGGCAGCAACUGUAUUUGAAUAAAAUGAUUUCUUAGUAUGAUUGUACAGUAAUGAAUGAAAGUGGAACAUGUUUCUUUUUGAAAGGGAGAGAAUUGACCAUUUAUUGUUGUGAUGUUUAAGUUAUAACUUAUUGAGCACUUUUAGUAGUGAUAACUGUUUUUAAACUUGCCUAAUACCUUUCUUGGGUAUUGUUUGUAAUGUGACUUAUUUAACGCCUUUUUUGUUUGUUUAAGUUGCUGCUUUAGGUUAACAGCGUGUUUUAGAAGAUUUAAAUUUCUUUCCUGUCUGCACAAUUAGCUAUUCAGAGCAAGAGGGCCUGAUUUUAUAGAAGCCCCUUGAAAAGAGGUCCAGAUGAGAGCAGAGAUACAGUGAGAAAUUAUGUGAUCUGUGUGUUGUGGGAAGAGAAUUUUCAAUAUGUAACUACGGAGCUGUAGUGCCAUUAGAAACUGUGAAUUUCCAAAUAAAUCUGAACACUUGUCUUUAUUAA